GUAAAUAACAGCGCUGGUGAUCCACCCGCGCGCACGGGCCGUCCUCUCCGCGCGGGGAGACGCGCGCAUCCACCAGCCCCGGCUGCUCGCCAGCCCCGGCCCCAGCCAUGGAAGAGCUCACGGCUUUUGUAUCCAAGUCUUUUGACCAGAAAAGCAAGGACGGUAACGGCGGAGGCGGAGGCGGCGGAGGUAAGAAGGAUUCCAUUACGUACCGGGAAGUUUUGGAGAGCGGACUGGCGCGCUCCCGGGAGCUGGGGACGUCGGAUUCCAGCCUCCAGGACAUCACGGAGGGCGGCGGCCACUGCCCGGUGCAUUUGUUCAAGGACCACGUAGACAAUGACAAGGAGAAACUGAAAGAAUUCGGCACCGCGAGAGUGGCAGAAGGGAUUUAUGAAUGCAAAGAGAAGCGCGAGGACGUGAAGUCGGAGGACGAGGACGGGCAGACCAAGCUGAAACAGAGGCGCAGCCGCACCAACUUCACGCUGGAGCAGCUGAACGAGCUCGAGCGACUCUUCGACGAGACCCAUUACCCCGACGCCUUCAUGCGCGAGGAGCUCAGCCAGCGCCUGGGGCUCUCCGAGGCGCGCGUGCAGGUUUGGUUCCAGAACCGGAGAGCCAAGUGCCGCAAACAAGAGAAUCAGAUGCAUAAAGGCGUCAUCUUGGGCACAGCCAACCACCUAGACGCCUGCCGAGUGGCACCCUACGUCAACAUGGGAGCCUUACGGAUGCCUUUCCAACAGGUCCAGGCUCAGCUGCAGCUGGAAGGCGUGGCCCACGCGCACCCGCACCUGCACCCGCACCUGGCGGCGCACGCGCCCUACCUGAUGUUCCCCCCGCCGCCCUUCGGGCUGCCCAUCGCGUCGCUGGCCGAGUCCGCCUCGGCCGCCGCCGUGGUCGCCGCCGCCGCCAAAAGCAACAGCAAGAAUUCCAGCAUCGCCGACCUGCGGCUCAAGGCGCGGAAGCACGCGGAGGCCCUGGGGCUCUGACCCGCCGCGCAGCCCCCCGCGCGCCCGGACUCCCGGGCUCCGCGCACCCCGCCUGCACCGCGCGUCCUGCACUCAACCCCGCCUGGAGCUCCUUCCGCGGCCACCGUGCUCCGGGCACCCCGGGAGCUCCUGCAAGAGGCCUGAGGAGGGAGGCUCCCGGGACCGUCCACGCACGACCCAGCCAGACCCUCGCGGAGAUGGUGCAGAAGGCGGAGCGGGUGAGCGGCCGUGCGUCCAGCCCGGGCCUCUCCAAGGCUGCCCGUGCGUCCUGGGACCCUGGAGAAGGGUAAACCCCCGCCUGGCUGCGUCUUCCUCUGCUAUACCCUAUGCAUGCGGUUAACUACACACGUUUGGAAGAUCCUUAGAGUCUAUUGAAACUGCAAAGAUCCCGGAGCUGGUCUCCGAUGAAAAUGCCAUUUCUUCGUUGCCAACGAUUUUCUUUACUACCAUGCUCCUUCCUUCAUCCCGAGAGGCUGCGGAACGGGUGUGGAUUUGAAUGUGGACUUCGGAAUCCCAGGAGGCAGGGGCCGGGCUCUCCUCCACCGCUCCCCCGGAGCCUCCCAGGCAGCAAUAAGGAAAUAGUUCUCUGGCUGAGGCUGAGGACGUGAACCGCGGGCUUUGGAAAGGGAGGGGAGGGAGACCCGAACCUCCCACGUUGGGACUCCCACGUUCCGGGGACCUGAAUGAGGACCGACUUUAUAACUUUUCCAGUGUUUGAUUCCCAAAUUGGGUCUGGUUUUGUUUUGGAUUGGUAUUUUUUUUUUUUUUUUUUUUUUUUUUUUUUUUUGCUGUGUUACAGGAUUCAGACGCAAAAGACUUGCAUAAGAGACGGACGCGUGGUUGCAAGGUGUCAUACUGAUAUGCAGCAUUAACUUUACUGACAUGGAGUGAAGUGCAAUAUUAUAAAUAUUAUAGAUUAAAAAAAAAAUAGCCGUGCACUCUUGACCCCGUCAGCGUCCAACGUGGAAAAGGCGUUACCUCUUCUCCCAGCGCUGGCCGCCUGGCCACUGAGGGCCCUUUGCAAAAAUCACGGGUGUAGAGAUGGCCCUGGGCGCGCUGGGAGUGUGGUUGUGUUUCUGAAGGGGAUAAAAGAGGGCACGGUGGUGCCAAGAUAUCAGUUUGGUACCUGAGCUGUUUCUGGUUGGGAAGCGUAAAAGCCAGGGAGAGAUCCAGAGAGUUUUCAAGUUUUUGCAGAUGUAGGUGGUUCCAGCUUUUCUUUCUCCCCUACUCCAUCUUCUGCGUUCCCCCAGUUCUUUUAUUUCUUUGUUUUUUAUUUUUGAGACAGAGACUUGCUUUGUCGCCCAGGCUGGAGUGCAGUGGCGCAAUGUCAGCUCACUGCCACCUCCGCCUCCCGGGUUCAAGCGAUGCUCCUGCCUCAGCCUCCCGAGUAGCUGGGACUACAGGCACCUGCCACCACCCCCGGCUAAUUUUUUGUAUUUAUAGUAGAGACGGGGUUUCACCGUGUUGGCCAGGCUCGUCUCGAACUCCUGACCUCAGGUGAUCUGCCCGCCUCGGCCUCCCAACGUGCCCCCAGUUUUAUAAACAGCAGAUAGCAACUUGUCGUCACAGCUGGCAUGGGCUGGACAGUUGCUUGAAAUGACCUAACCAAAAACAUUCAAGGGUUCUGCCCCCAGAUUUCGGGAGAUCCACGUUCCAUGUUCUGAUUGGUUUUCUGGGAACACAGCAAGGGGUUUGGUGACCUCCGAGAAGAUCCAUCUGCAUGAUUGGCAUUAGUUACCACAGCCUGCCCAGAGAGAAACUAUCUUCUCCCAACAUUUACUAACAUCCACUGGUCAACUCUCUUAUUUCCAUAACACAUUUGCAUCUUUCUGGAUUCAAGCUUGGUGGUUUUCUUUCCUAACUUCUGAUUUAGAUACUUCUCCCUGAGGUGGGGAUAAAAGAAAAAAAAAAACAACUUCUUUUUUUCUUCCGCAUAACACUUUCUAUCUUGUCACUGAGCUGAACUGUAGAUCCAUUUGGACCCGUCUCAUUUGUAUCUUCUGAUAUUCUUUAUACAAACCAAAAGUCCCCUUCAACAUUUUUUAUGUCAAAAUGUUACAACCGCUGUAAAAUGACGGAGAGAGAGAGAAAGAAUCCCAGACAUUAACGGUAUUAGAGAGUUUGCCUCAUUCAUCCAUUUUUCUUAAAAGCUGGAAAUUAAAAAAAAAAAAGAGAGAGAGAGGCUUUAAUAGUUAAGCUGAAAUUUUUAUCGAAAAGAAGAAUUGCAUUUUGAAUCUUUGGGAAGUAGGUUCAUUCAUCAGAGUAUGUAACCCUUUGGAAAAGUGGUUGGUAAGAUAUGUACAGCCCUAGAUUUUUUUUUUUUAACCAAAAAGGCUGAGUAAUUUUGAAAAAUCGAAACAUAACAGUGUGUCAUCAUUUCCUCCCAAGAAAAAGCUCACUCCACGUGAGUAGAAAGACAUCUACCUGGUCCCUGUAGAAUCUGAACGUUUCUCUUUAGAGACGGAAUUUCAAUCUUGUCCCCCAGGCUGGAGUGCAGUGGCACAAUCUCGGCUCACCGCAACCUCCGCCUCCCGGGUUCAAGCCAUUCUCCUGCCUCAGCCUCCCGAGUAGCUGGGAUUACAGGCACCUGCCACCAGGCCUGGGUAACUUUCUGGUAUUUUUAGUAGAGACAGGGUUUCAGCCUCCCGAGUAGCUGGGAUUACAGGCACCUGCCACCAGGCCUGGGUAACUUUCUGGUAUUUUUAGUAGAGACAGGGUUUCAGCCUCCCGAGUAGCUGGGAUUACAGGCACCUGCCACCAGGCCUGGGUAACUUUCUGGUAUUUUUAGUAGAGACAGGGUUUCAGCCUCCCGAGUAGCUGGGAUUACAGGCACCUGCCACCAGGCCUGGGUAACUUUCUGGUAUUUUUAGUAGAGACAGGGUUUCGGCCUCCCGAGUAGCUGGGAUUACAGGCACCUGCCACCAGGCCUGGGUAACUUUCUGGUAUUUUUAGUAGAGACAGGGUUUCGGCCUCCCGAGUAGCUGGGAUUACAGGCACCUGCCACCAGGCCUGGGUAACUUUCUGGUAUUUUUAGUAGAGACAGGGUUUCAGCCUCCCGAGUAGCUGGGAUUACAGGCACCUGCCACCAGGCCUGGGUAACUUUCUGGUAUUUUUAGUAGAGACAGGGUUUCGGCCUCCCGAGUAGCUGGGAUUACAGGCACCUGCCACCAGGCCUGGGUAACUUUCUGGUAUUUUUAGUACAGACAGGGUUUCAGCCUCCCGAGUAGCUGGGAUUACAGGCACCUGCCACCAGGCCUGGGUAACUUUCUGGUAUUUUUAGUAGAGACAGGGUUUCGGCCUCCCGAGUAGCUGGGAUUACAGGCACCUGCCACCAGGCCUGGGUAACUUUCUGGUAUUUUUAGUAGAGACAGGGUUUCGGCCUCCCGAGUAGCUGGGAUUACAGGCACCUGCCACCAGGCCUGGGUAACUUUCUGGUAUUUUUAGUAGAGACAGGGUUUCGGCCUCCUGAGUAGCUGGGAUUACAGGCACCUGCCACCAGGCCUGGGUAACUUUCUGGUAUUUUUAGUAGAGACAGGGUUUCAGCCUCCCGAGUAGCUGGGAUUACAGGCACCUGCCACCAGGCCUGGGUAACUUUCUGGUAUUUUUAGUACAGACAGGGUUUCGGCCUCCUGAGUAGCUGGGAUUACAGGCACCUGCCACCAGGCCUGGGUAACUUUCUGGUAGUUUUAGUAGAGACAGGGUUUCAGCCUCCCGAGUAGCUGGGAUUACAGGCACCUGCCACCAGGCCUGGGUAAUUUUUUUGCAUUUUUGGUAGAGACAGGUUUUUGCUGUGUUGGCCCGGCUGGUCUCAAACUCCUGACCUCAGGUUGACCUGCCCGCUUUGUCCCUCGCAAAGUGCUGGGAUUACAGGCGUGAGCCACCGCACCUGGCCUGAAUCUGAACUUUUAAAAGGGAGUUACUGACUCUCAACUGUGCGGGGACGGUUUCAGUUUGAUUUAAUAUGGAAAGAGGGCCAAGUGUCAUCCUCACAAAUGGGUCCCCGAAGCAGAUCAAACGCAGAGAACUGUGAGGGUGGGACACGAGUGUCUGUGGACACUGGCUGCCUUUGGCUUUUCUCCUGCGAGAGAAGUUGGGUGACUUUCUGUAGGUGGAUGAGUGAUCCCUGAAUGAGUGUGGGGUACGUGUAUGCUAGCUGCUUCUUUCUCCCUGAAACUCUCGGAUGGAAGGAAGUAAGAAAUUCAGCUUGGGCUGUGACCAGUUCUCACCACCAACGCCCUCUUCUCUCUCCCUUCUCCUUCCUUCCUUCCUUCCUUUCUUUCUUUUUCUUUCUUUCUCUCUUUCUUUCUUUUCUUUCUUUCUGUUUCUUUCCUUUUUAUCUUUCUCUCUUUUUCUUUCUCUUUUCCUUUUUUGUUUCUUUCUUUCUUUUUCUUUCUUUCUUUUUCUUUCUUCUUUCUUUCUUCGAUGAAGUCUCACUCUGUCACCCAGGCUGGAGUGCAGUGGUGCAAUCCCAGCUCACUGCAUCCUCUACCUCCUGGCUUCAAGAAAUUCUCCUGCCUCAGCCUCCCAAGUAGCUGGGAUGACAGGCACCCACCACCAUUCCCGGAUAAUUUUUGUAUUUUUUAGUAGAGACCGGGUUUCGCCAUGUUGGCCAGGCUGGUCUUGAACUCCUGACCUCACAUGAUCCACCCGCCUCAGCCUCCCAGAGUGCUGGGAUUACGGGGUGAGGCACCGCGCCCGGCCUCCUCUCUCUUUUUCUGAGAUGUUUAGGAAGGACUGGGCUGAUGGGGACCCUCUGUAUGUGAUGUGCGUGGGUUUGGUUUCCCGGAAGGCCCUCCAGAGACACGUUUGCGUGAACAUUCAGCAUGGAAACAACAUACGUCUCUCCACAGGAGGUGAGAAAUUGAAUUUAUGGGGUGGGUGUACGCUGGCGAUUCUUGGUGCUUUUUGCUCAAAACAAGGUUCUUUUGAAAGUCACGUUCCUGCUUUCCCUGUGGCUUCCCGGUGAGCUCGCUCGCAGAGCAAGGAAUACCACCCAGAGAGCAACGUGGGCUGUGUUCCGAUGUAACGCCGUUGCAGAGAGAGGAUUUGGUGUGUGAGAUCCGUACCAGCUCCAGCACACUGAUAGGAACACGUUGCUGGCCGAACUGAACGAUGCUGGGUUGGGUCCUGAUUGAUACGUAUUUUCUUCCCUCCUCUCCCCAAAACUUGGCCAAAUAGUCCGUGGAGGGUUGUCAGUCGCCGCAGUUGAGCAAAAAACACUUCUUCCUUUGAGUGGCUGUUCUGGUGAAAUCUGUUUCUGACAUAUCCACUUUUCUCUCUCUUUUCUCUCUCUCUGACUGCGAAGCACCCACAGGGAGAAGGAAUUGGAUGUAUCGGAUGUUGCUAUUAGAUUUUCUUUCUCCGUUCGAGUCUCUGACUGGUGCAUACUUUGCAAAGGUGUGUUCCUGGCAAUUGCCAAGAGUUAGAAAAAUGCACCUUCUCUGGUGGCCGUUGGGGUGUUGUUUCACAGGCAGUGGUGACAGGGCCCCUUGGCUGUGGCUGUCUUCUCCAGCGCCGUGGAUAAAGAGAUGGGACAGAUUCUGUGCCUCUGUACGAUUUAGAGCGUAACUGACCGCGUCCAACACCCGUUUUUCCACUUACAAAGCUGGUGGUGCGACGGGCUUGGUGUCUCCCGUACGGGAAGGAGGCCUUUGGGCCGCUCCAAAGACGCCCUGUCGUAGGAAUGGCCUCUCCAUCCCGCCAAAGUCCAGCCAGGCCCCCGAAAUGGUCCCAUUUCCUUGGAAGCCUGAGUUUCUGUUCUGGUCUUGCUGCUGUCCUUGGCCACGUCAGCACGUGGGAGCAUCUGUGGAUACCGCAGAGUCUGGGGACAGCUGGGCGUUUAACCGAAAUGAAGCCGAGACGGGUUUCAGGUUUUGGUGCCAAGCUCUGGUCAGGAUGAAAGGGAAAUACCAGAGUCCUCUGUCCUCGCCUCUGGGUUUCAUGCUGACCUUUCUAACAUUUGUUUUCCCCUAAGAACAAGCAGAAGCCUCCAGCUCCCUUUAGCUCCACAGUUUUCCCGGGGACAUAGCGAGGAUGGCACACGGCAGCCACUCCCACGACACACAUUUCGGAGGCACUUUGCUGGAAGCCGCUUGUCUCCUCCAGCUUUGGGAGGUCUGGGGAGGAGAGAGGCUUUCGGUGGACACGUUUGACAUUAAAAAAAAAAAAAAAAAAAAAAAAAAACUGGUGCCUAAUUUAUUAAAGAGAAUUAGCUUAGCGAGUAUAUGCUGAUAUUCUUCGACACACGUGGGUAAGUUGAUGCCAUUUAUAAAUGUUUUAUUGAAAUUUGAUAUUUAAUGAGAAGCCGGUUAAGGAAUGUAGACAAUAUCCCGUUUCAAAGCUAUGAAAUGUGCUAUUUAUUGAAAGGGGAUGUGGCUUCACGAGUUCAGCCCAUUGUACGUGCAGGUCCCGUGGGAAGGAGGCAAAAGCCCCUGCUUCUUACUUUGUGAUGUAUGUGCAUUUGUUAUUUAUUUUUUUUUCCUUGGUCGGACGUUCAUAAAUAUGUACUAUUUUAAUUAUGUCGAGUGUAAAUUUGACAUCGCGUUGCAUUUAUUUUUAUAUUUCUGAAAACUGUUGCUUUUUCUUUUUCCCUCCCCCAUUGACGACAUAGCGGCCCCCGCGUCCGGGUUACAAAUACAUCUACAGAUAUUUUCAGGGAUUGCUUCAGAUGAAAACAAAUCACACACCGUUUCCCAAACCAACAGUCUUCACAUUUCUAUCCCUCUGUUAUUGUCGGCAGGCGGUGAGGGGUAGAAAAAAAACAAACAAACAAACAGAAAAAAAAACCAAAAAAAACCACCCUGAGUUUCUCUGGUGACGCCCUCAUUCUCCUAACGUUCAAUAAUCUCAAUGUUGAGUUGCAGCAACAGACUGUAUUUUUGUGACGCCCCGUAGUAUGAAUGUACAUCUUGUAAAACUGAGAUAUAAAUAAACUUAUAAAUAUUUGUA